AUGGCCCUCCCGACACCCUCGGACAGCACCCUCCCCGCGGAAGCCCGGGGACGAGGACGGCGACGGAGACUCGUUUGGACCCCGAGCCAAAGCGAGGCCCUGCGAGCCUGCUUUGAGCGGAACCCGUACCCGGGCAUCGCCACCAGAGAACGGCUGGCCCAGGCCAUCGGCAUUCCGGAGCCCAGGGUCCAGAUUUGGUUUCAGAAUGAGAGGUCACGCCAGCUGAGGCAGCACCGGCGGGAAUCUCGGCCCUGGCCCGGGAGACGCGGCCCGCCAGAAGGCCGGCGAAAGCGGACCGCCGUCACCGGAUCCCAGACCGCCCUGCUCCUCCGAGCCUUUGAGAAGGAUCGCUUUCCAGGCAUCGCCGCCCGGGAGGAGCUGGCCAGAGAGACGGGCCUCCCGGAGUCCAGGAUUCAGAUCUGGUUUCAGAAUCGAAGGGCCAGGCACCCGGGACAGGGUGGCAGGGCGCCCGCGCAGGCAGGCGGCCUGUGCAGCGCGGCCCCCGGCGGGGGUCACCCUGCUCCCUCGUGGGUCGCCUUCGCCCACACCGGCGCGUGGGGAACGGGGCUUCCCGCACCCCACGUGCCCUGCGCGCCUGGGGCUCUCCCACAGGGGGCUUUCGUGAGCCAGGCAGCGAGGGCCGCCCCCGCGCUGCAGCCCAGCCAGGCCGCGCCGGCAGAGGGGAUCUCCCAACCUGCCCCGGCGCGCGGGGAUUUCGCCUACGCCGCCCCGGCUCCUCCGGACGGGGCGCUCUCCCACCCUCAGGCUCCUCGGUGGCCUCCGCACCCGGGCAAAAGCCGGGAGGACCGGGACCCGCAGCGCGACGGCCUGCCGGGCCCCUGCGCGGUGGCACAGCCUGGGCCCGCUCAAGCGGGGCCGCAGGGCCAAGGGGUGCUUGCGCCACCCACGUCCCAGGGGAGUCCGUGGUGGGGCUGGGGCCGGGGUCCCCAGGUCGCCGGGGCGGCGUGGGAACCCCAAGCCGGGGCAGCUCCACCUCCCCAGCCCGCGCCCCCGGACGCCUCCGCCUCCGCGCGGCAGGGGCAGAUGCAAGGCAUCCCGGCGCCCUCCCAGGCGCUCCAGGAGCCGGCGCCCUGGUCUGCACUCCCCUGCGGCCUGCUGCUGGAUGAGCUCCUGGCGAGCCCGGAGUUUCUGCAGCAGGCGCAACCUCUCCUAGAAACGGAGGCCCCGGGGGAGCUGGAGGCCUCGGAAGAGGCCGCCUCGCUGGAAGCACCCCUCAGCGAGGAAGAAUACCGGGCUCUGCUGGAGGAGCUUUAGGACGCGGGGUUGGGACGGGGUCGGGUGGUUCGGGGCAGGGCGGUGGCCUCUCUUUCGCGGGGAACACCUGGCUGGCUACGGAGGGGCGUGUCUCCGCCCCGCCCCCUCCACCGGGCUGACCGGCCUGGGAUUCCUGCCUUCUAGGUCUAGGCCCGGUGAGAGACUCCACUCCGCGGAGAACUGCCUUUCUUUCCUGGGCAUCCCGGGGAUCCCAGAGCCGGCCCAGGUACCAGCAGACCUGCGCGCAGUGCGCACCCCGGCUGACGUGCAAGGGAGCUCGCUGGCCUCUCUGUGCCCUUGUUCUUCCGUGAAAUUCUGGCUGAAUGUCUCCCCCCACCUUCCGACGCUGUCUAGGCAAACCUGGAUUAGAGUUACAUCUCCUGGAUGAUUAGUUCAGAGAUAUAUUAAAAUGCCCCCUCCCUGUGGAUCCUAUAG